GUCCCGGGACUGGGAAGAAACGGCGGCCGGGAGGGGGCUCCGGGGACCAUGGGGCUCCUGACCAUUCUGAAGAAGAUGAAGCAGAAAGAGCGGGAGCUGCGACUGCUCAUGCUUGGCCUGGACAAUGCUGGAAAGACAACCAUCCUGAAGAAGUUCAAUGGGGAGGACAUCGACACCAUCUCCCCAACGCUGGGCUUCAACAUCAAGACCCUGGAGCACCGAGGAUUCAAGCUGAACAUCUGGGAUGUGGGUGGCCAGAAGUCCCUGCGGUCCUACUGGCGGAACUACUUUGAGAGCACCGAUGGCCUCAUCUGGGUAGUGGACAGCGCAGACCGCCAGCGCAUGCAGGACUGCCAGCGGGAGCUCCAGAGCCUGCUGGUGGAGGAGCGCCUGGCCGGAGCAACCCUCCUCAUCUUUGCUAAUAAGCAGGACCUGCCUGGAGCACUGUCCUCUAACGCCAUCCGCGAGGUCCUGGAGCUGGACUCCAUCCGCAGCCACCACUGGUGCAUCCAGGGCUGCAGCGCCGUCACCGGGGAGAACCUGCUGCCGGGCAUCGACUGGCUCCUGGAUGACAUUUCCAGCCGCAUUUUCACAGCUGACUGAACCACUCCAGAUGCCCCCCACCUAGCAGUCCAGGUCCCUCAACCUUCACCAAACACUACCCAUGGGGGGUUGGGAGUCAGCCGGCCAAACUAACACUCCCCCUCCUCCACCCCAGCCUGCUGCUGCUACUGCUGCCCGCUGCUGCUCUGUGGCCACCCGGCUCCCAUGGCGGGAGGGCUGUGCCCUGGCUGUCUCUCUGGCUCCUGACCUGGCCUUUGGCUACCAUACCAAGAAGAGAGGGCUGGGCGGGGAGGAGCUGCUACUGCUGCUACCGAGGCUGUGGGCCUCAUCCUUCACUCAGUUGUGAAAUAAACCGCUCCUUGCCCCGA